GAAUCAUCCCUAUAAUGUAGUGAAACUUUAGAAAGAAGAGCCGGGAGGAUGUAUUGGUUGUUAGGAAAAUGUAGGCUACCAGUAGAAAAUGACAUUCUCUAUUAAUAAGAUCUGAGGGCUUUCUGGGAAUUGUCUUGACAGAGAACCUCAGCUGGACAAAGCAGCCUUGAUCUGAGUGAGCUAACUGACACAAUGAAACUGUCAGGCAUGUUUCUGCUCCUCUCUCUGGCUCUUUUCUGCUUUUUAACAGGUGUCUUCAGUCAGGGAGGACAGGUUGACUGUGGUGAGUUCCAGGACCCCAAGGUCUACUGCACUCGGGAAUCUAACCCACACUGUGGCUCUGAUGGCCAGACAUAUGGCAAUAAAUGUGCCUUCUGUAAGGCCAUAGUGAAAAGUGGUGGAAAGAUUAGCCUAAAGCAUCCUGGAAAAUGCUGAGUUAAAGCCAAUGUUUCUUGGUGACUUGCCAGCUUUUGCAGCCUUCUUUUCUCACUUCUGCUUAUACUUUUGCUGGUGGAUUCCUUUAAUUCAUAAAGACAUACCUACUCUGCCUGGGUCUUGAGGAGUUCAAUGUAUGUCUAUUUCUCUUGAUUCACUUGUCAAUAAAGUACAUUCUGCAAAAGCA